UUCAGAAUCACGCCGGCCUCAUUCUACCGCUGCUCUCUCCUGGAUCUCGGCCACGGAUCUUUUGCUCGCGAAAGUUCCUCCGUCUAGCUGCACACAACGCUGCUGCAGGAAACCGAGGUAAGGGAUUUGCCGAGACUUAGCUCCACCACACUCCCCGAGGCCCCGCCCCUCCUCUCUGGCCCUCCCCUAGGCCCAGGUGUCUCGCGUUGCACGUGCAGUUGUUGUGGUUCUACGUCACGUGGUCCCGGAAGUUCAAGACAGACCCGCCUCAAACAUGGCGGCGCCCAGCGCGCGAGGACGUGAUCCGCUUCUGCUCCGGCUUGGAUUGUAGCCUUGACGAGGUCUGAGCGACCAUGGACCGGCCGGGGUUCGUGGCAGCGCUGGUGGCUGGUGGGGUAGCAGGUGUUUCUGUUGACUUGAUAUUAUUUCCUCUGGAUACCAUUAAAACCAGGCUGCAGAGUCCCCAAGGAUUUAGUAAGGCUGGUGGUUUUCAUGGAAUAUAUGCUGGCGUUCCUUCUGCUGCUAUUGGAUCCUUUCCUAAUGCUGCUGCAUUUUUUAUCACCUAUGAAUAUGUGAAGUGGUUUUUGCAUGCUGAUUCAUCUUCAUAUUUGACACCUAUGAAACAUAUGUUGGCUGCCUCUGCUGGAGAAGUGGUUGCCUGCCUGAUUCGAGUUCCAUCUGAAGUGGUUAAGCAGAGGGCACAGGUAUCUGCUUCUACAAGAACAUUUCAGAUUUUCUCUAACAUCUUAUAUGAAGAGGGUAUCCAAGGGUUGUAUCGAGGCUAUAAAAGCACAGUUUUAAGAGAGAUAAAUUCACUGAUAGAAUUUUUCAGUAAAUCCUAAGAAAAUAAUGUGAUGGGGGAUCUACAAGACUUGAACCAAAUCUUGACCUGAGUGAGAGUGGAGCACAAUUUCUGAGUGUUAGAGGAUUCUAAAGGAUAGAAAUGGAACUGUUUGUAUGGGCAGAACACAAUGAGAUGCUUCUAAAACAGCCAUUAAUAUUGAUUUCAGCAUCCUUUUUCGUCUGGCCUUUGUGAGGGGUGCUUAAAAAUGUUUUGACUGAUUGUAGUCUGUCCUUUUUUGUUCCCUGUGCUGCAUCAUAUGUUCUGAGAAACAGUAGAGUAGGUGGGAAAAGGUUGAUAAUCUUUGGCCUUGAAGUGGUUUUGGUAUACAUAGCCAAGUAACUAGCAGAUAAUUUAUUGACUAGUGGAGAAGCAGAAAUUUUUGUGAGGAUUUUUUUUUUUCCCUUUUUGAAUAUACUCUGCUUUUUGUUAUUCAACUUGUCAGUGCAAAACUGACAUUAUAGAAGAACGCACUAGAGGGCGCACAAUGCCUGUAUUUUAAAUGUUGGUGGCAAAAACCUCAGCAUGAACUUGGAAGCUGCUUCCUGGCACUGUUUGAAAAAAAAAAAAAAAGGUUCAAAUUAGAAAAUGUAAAUUUAAGCAUAAUAGUGUUUUCCGAUCAAGAUACCUGAAUGGAUAAAUUUGUGUUAUCUUUUGAUACAUAUGUACAUGGAGUUGUAUUUAUUUGGGUUCUAAUUUUUUAAAACUUUUACCAUGGAAAAAUUUAAAGACACACAAAAAAGAUUACUAAAAUGAAUCCCUGUAGUCUCAUCAAUUACCAGCUCUUGAGCAGUAUUGUUCCAUCUAUACCAAACCCUGCUUCCCACAUGUCUGUAUGAUAUUGAAGCAAAUACCAGACAUUCUGAUUUCAUCCAGAAAUACGUCACUAUGCAUCUCUAAAAGAUAACUGUAAAUAUGUAUAAUGUAUCAAAAAUGAGUGUCAUAACAGAAAGACAAAUAUUGUAUUAUAUGUGUAAACUAAGAAAGUAAAAUUCAUAGAAGCAGAGAGUAGAACCAUGGUUCUCGGGUGUUAGGGGGUGGGUAAAUGGGGAGAUGUUGUUCAAAGGGUACAAAUUGUCAGUUAUAGGAUCAGCAGGUUCUGGGUAUUUAAGGUACAGCAUGAAAAGUGAUGGAUGUGUUAAUUAAUUUGAUUGUGGUAAUCAUUACACAUUGUGUAUCAAAUCAUCACAUUGCUCACUUUAAUAUAUAUAAUCUUUAUUUGUCAUUUAUUUUAAAAAACGAAUAUCAUAGUCUAGAAGUAUUUCCCCAAAGCUAUUUAUCACUUACAAAGGGGAAAAUAGUAAUUUUACAGUUGGAAAGACUGGCAGUCACUAUUUUAUCCAAGUGAUCAAGAUUAGCAUCACCAGUAAUAAGAUUAUAUUAACAUCAUACAUCUCUAAUAUAAUGCACCAAGAAGGACACAAUGUCACUUCUUUGGUCUUCUUGCCAAAGAUGCAUAAUCUCAGUGUGAUCAUGAGAAAACAUCACACAAACCGAGAUUGAGAGACAUUGUACAGAAUUGUCAAAGUUAUGAUAAAGAAAGAUGAAAGAACUGCCACAAAUAAGAGAAGACUAAGGAGACACAACAAGUAAAUGCAGUGUAGGAUCCUGGAUUUGAUCCUGGAACAGAAAAGAUUUUGGGAAAAACUGGUAACAUUCAAAAUCUGUAAUUUAGCUAUUAGCAUUGCAGCAAAACUGGUAGCUGGUUUUGAUAAGUGUACUGUAGUUAAUUUAUUAACAUUAGAGAAGCCAGCAUAUAUGUGAACUCUGCUAUUUAUGCAACUUUUAUGAGAGUUUGUUUUUAAAAAACAAACUAAAAUGCCACAUUUGGACAUUGUAUGAAGUACUUGUUUUUAGAGUCAUCUUCUAAAAUAAUGACAAGUUAAAUUUAAAAUUUAAUUUCUUUUAUUGUUAACUUGUAUUAAAAUAAUAUAUGCAAUUAGUAACAACCCAAAUAAUGUAGAAGGACUUAAGAUGAAAAACAACAGUCUCCUGCCCAUCCCUCUCCAUUCUGGUUCCACUCUCUAGAGGUAGCCUUUAUUUUUUAUUUUUUAAAAUUUUAACUGUUUUAUUUUUAGUUCUUAUUUCAUCGGUGCUUUCAGAUAAUAUAUUAUUUAAAUGUCUGUUUUAAAAUUUGUCAGUAGAUAAAGUUUGUUGAGUCUUUGGGAUGGAAGAUGUGAUUAAGCUCACAUUAUGUUCUUCCCCAACCCUGUCUCAUCCUAGCAUUCCAGUUAUAUAAAUUUCAUUCCUCUGUUCAUUUUAGAAACUUUAAGUUAUAUAUUCGUUUCUUUAUUUCUUAUCCUACGAACUUUCUGCAUCUUACAACUUUCUCUUGACAUGAUGAGGCUGUUGCUUUCUUUUUGCCACCUUGUCCUCCUUAACCUGCAAAUUUCACUUUCUGGAAAGACUUCUCUCAACUAUACUUUCAUUGUACAUUGUCAAGAGGGUUGACAAUUUCAUCCUGUCUUUUACCCUCAGUCACUUCUUUCAUAGCUCUUCUGUAUUGAUUCUAAAAGUGGAGUACCGGUGAACUAGUGUUUGUAUUAUUGAGAAGACUUCAUGAAUGAUCAGACCAUGUAGUGUGCUAAGGCUGUAUUUUUUUUUGUGUGUGGGACUUACACCCUGAGAGAUGGUUUCAGCAUCAGAAUCAAAUAGACCUUCUUGCACUCUAUCAGUUGCUAAAAUUUAAUUUCCAACAUUUGGGGCAUGAGCUUGUCUUUUUUUCUUGGAGUUUCUAAUUGCCUUUUCUGUAUGAAAAAGGCAUUAUUUGCAUUAUUUUUAGGUAUGACAACUUUGAAAACAUACUGUCUUUUGUCCUGAGUCCCCUUUUACCCUGGGAAUCUUGGAAUCUUUCAUUCUCCUGUUCUAAUCCUGUGUUAAUAUUCACUGUGUUUGGGCUUCUAUUCUUGGGUCAGAUUUGCUGUUUCCUGAAGGCCGCAUAGCAUAGUGGUUCAGACCAGGGCUUUGUGGUCAGGCAGCCCAGGUUUUGCCAACAGCUCUGCCUCUGUUAAACUUACACCUGGUGCUACAGUGUCCUCAUUGAAUGAAAAUGCUUUCAGAUAUGAAAAAUAUAAGAAUUUAGUCCAUUUGUUUGAAGGCUUUUAUUUGAUUCUGAUUUUUUUGGGGAGGUGGGGUCAGGUAAUUAUCUUUCUCUAGUGCCUAUUAUUUUACAAAUAUCUCAUUAAAGACAGCCGAUGAUAACCAUUCUCAUGA